GACAGACCGUGUGUUUCCAAAAUGGCGGCAGCGAUGGAUGUGGAUACCCCGAGCGGCACCAACAGCGGCGCGGGCAAGAAGCGCUUUGAAGUGAAAAAGUGGAAUGCAGUAGCCCUCUGGGCCUGGGAUAUUGUGGUUGAUAACUGUGCCAUCUGCAGGAACCACAUUAUGGAUCUUUGCAUAGAAUGUCAAGCUAACCAGGCGUCCGCUACUUCAGAAGAGUGUACUGUCGCAUGGGGAGUCUGUAACCAUGCUUUUCACUUCCACUGCAUCUCUCGCUGGCUCAAAACACGACAGGUGUGUCCAUUGGACAACAGAGAGUGGGAAUUCCAAAAGUAUGGGCACUAGGAAAAGACUUCUUCCAUCAAGCUUAAUUGUUUUGUUAUUCAUUUAAUGACUUUCCCUGCUGUUACCUAAUUACAAAUUGGAUGGAACUGUGUUUUUUUCUGCUUUGUUUUUUCAGUUUGCUGUUUCUGUAGCCAUAUUGUAUUCUGUGUCAAAUAAAGUCCAGUUGGAUUCUGGAACGGAUGCUCUCUCUUGUGUAUGUGAACAAAGUGAACAUAAAUGAAGAGUCUCCCCUUCCAAGGCUGAAAACUCAGCUUUUGAAAGUGAAAUGUUUGUUCAUCGGGGCCAGAGCAGGGUUGUCCUCUGAGCGCAUCACUUAGUGACGAGGAAUCCAACAGCUCAAGGCAGAGUGUGGAUCACCGGCUCCCGAAAACAGCAGUCAGCCCUUCUUUCUCCUGUGUGACAGCAGUGGGCAGCUGAAAGAGGGAAGAAUGUGGGAUUCAGUCAUCAAACCCAGUUCUGAGUCCUGGUUCCACAGCUUGGGUACUGAUGGCAAUCUUGGCCAAGUUGUCUCUCUACUCUGAACUUUCCUCCUCUGUACUGUGGGCUUCUGAGGACUAAGUGGCAUCAUGUGGGCACAGAGAGAAGCUUUGUAAAAUGUAAAACCGCUAUACAAAUGUGACCUUUGGUUGUGUAUGACAGCAGUCCCCAACCUUUUUGCCACCAGGGAUUGGUUUCAUGGAAGACGAUUUUUCCAUGGACCGGGGGUGGGGCGGGGGUGUGCUUGGGGAUGGUUUUGGAACUGUUCCACCUGAGAUCAUGAGGCAGUAGAUGGACCGCGCAACCUAGAUCCCUCACAUGCACGGUUCGCCAAUAGGGUUGAA